AAGUAAAGGAUCCUGAGAACUGAAGGCAAACAGAGCUCCAGGAGUCCAAGACAGAGCCACAGACCACGAGGAUCCCUGGCCCAGGUCUUGGACUUCAUUCCAUUUUCUGUUGAGUAAUAAACUCAACGUUGAAAAUGUCCUUUGUGGGGGAGAACUCAGGAGUGAAAAUGGGCUCUGAGGACUGGGAAAAAGAUGAACCCCAGUGCUGCUUAGAAGACCCGGCUGGAAGCCCCCUGGAACCAGGCCCAAGCCUCCCCACCAUGAAUUUUGUUCACACAAGUCCAAAGGUGAAGAACUUAAACCCGAAGAAAUUCAGCAUUCAUGACCAGGAUCACAAAGUACUGGUCCUGGACUCUGGGAAUCUCAUAGCAGUUCCAGAUAAAAACUACAUACGCCCAGAGAUCUUCUUUGCAUUAGCCUCAUCCUUGAGCUCAGCCUCUGCGGAGAAAGGAAGUCCGAUUCUCCUGGGGGUCUCUAAAGGGGAGUUUUGUCUCUACUGUGACAAGGAUAAAGGACAAAGUCAUCCAUCCCUUCAGCUGAAGAAGGAGAAACUGAUGAAGCUGGCUGCCCAAAAGGAAUCAGCACGCCGGCCCUUCAUCUUUUAUAGGGCUCAGGUGGGCUCCUGGAACAUGCUGGAGUCGGCGGCUCACCCCGGAUGGUUCAUCUGCACCUCCUGCAAUUGUAAUGAGCCUGUUGGGGUGACAGAUAAAUUUGAGAACAGGAAACACAUUGAAUUUUCAUUUCAACCAGUUUGCAAAGCUGAAAUGAGCCCCAGUGAGGUCAGCGAUUAGGAAACUGCCCCAUUGAACGCCUUCCUCGCUAAUUUGAACUAAUUGUAUAAAAACACCAAACCUGCUCACUAAA